ACAGUGGGCAGCCCGAUUUUCUGCUGAGUAGGCGCUGUGAUUUCAGAAUGUCUGGGCGAGGUAAAGGUGGCAAGGGGCUGGGUAAGGGAGGCGCCAAGCGCCACCGGAAGGUGCUGCGGGACAAUAUCCAAGGCAUUACAAAGCCGGCGAUUCGCCGUCUCGCCCGACGUGGGGGCGUCAAGCGCAUUUCUGGUCUCAUCUACGAGGAGACCCGGGGAGUCCUCAAAGUCUUCCUGGAGAACGUGAUCCGUGACGCGGUGACUUACACGGAGCACGCCAAGCGCAAGACCGUCACGGCCAUGGAUGUGGUGUACGCGCUGAAACGCCAGGGUCGCACCCUUUAUGGUUUCGGCGGUUGAGCUGUCCCCACAGCUUCUCUACAGACUCCAAAAGGCCCUUUUCAGGGCCCCCA